GCAGCGCUGGUCGCAGCCCUCAGCUGCGCCGGGCGGUUCCGGCUCCUCCCUCUCCUUGUGCCUCAGCGCCACCAUGGUGCUGGAGUCGGUGGUCGCGGACUUGCUGAACCGCUUCCUGGGGGACUAUGUGGAGAACCUGAACAAGUCCCAGCUGAAGCUGGGCAUCUGGGGCGGAAAUGUGGCUUUAGAUAAUCUACAGAUAAAAGAAAAUGCCCUGAGUGAAUUGGAUGUUCCUUUUAAAGUCAAGGCUGGCCAAAUUGAUAAAUUAACUUUGAAGAUUCCUUGGAAGAACCUUUAUGGAGAAGCAGUUGUUGCGACCCUGGAAGGAUUAUACCUGCUUGUUGUCCCUGGAGCAAGUAUUAAGUAUGAUGCUGUAAAAGAAGAAAAAUCCUUGCAGGAUGUUAAACAGAAAGAGCUAUCCCGAAUUGAAGAAGCCCUUCAAAAAGCAGCAGAAAAAGGCACACAUUCAGGGGAGUUCAUAUAUGGCUUGGAGAACUUUGUUUACAAGGACAUCAAGCCUGGACGUAAACGUAAAAAGCACAAAAAACAUUUUAAGAAACCUUUUAAAGGUCUUGAUCGUUCAAAAGAUAAGCCAAAAGAAGCCAAAAAGGAUACAUUUGUGGAAAAAUUGGCAACUCAAGUAAUAAAAAAUGUACAAGUAAAAAUCACAGAUAUUCACAUUAAAUAUGAAGAUGAUGUCACUGAUCCAAAGCGGCCUCUUUCAUUUGGUGUCACACUGGGAGAGCUUAGUCUACUGACUGCAAAUGAACACUGGACUCCAUGCAUAUUAAAUGAAGCAGACAAAAUUAUAUACAAGCUUAUACGACUUGAUAGUCUUAGCGCCUACUGGAAUGUAAAUUGCAGCAUGUCUUACCAGAGAUCAAGGGAACAGAUUUUGGAUCAGCUGAAAAAUGAAAUUCUUACAAGUGGAAAUAUACCCCCAAAUUAUCAAUACAUUUUCCAGCCAAUAUCAGCCUCUGCAAAACUCUACAUGAAUCCUUAUGCAGAAUCAGAGCUCAAAACGCCCAAACUGGAUUGCAACAUAGAAAUACAAAAUAUUGCCAUUGAACUGACCAAACCUCAGUACUUAAGUAUGAUUGACCUUUUGGAGUCAGUGGAUUAUAUGGUUAGGAAUGCGCCUUAUAGGAAAUACAAGCCUUAUUUACCACUUCAUACCAAUGGUCGACGAUGGUGGAAAUAUGCAAUUGAUUCUGUUCUUGAAGUUCAUAUAAGAAGGUAUACACAGAUGUGGUCAUGGAGUAACAUAAAAAAGCACAGGCAGUUACUCAAGAGUUAUAAAAUUGCCUACAAAAACAAGUUAACACAGUCUAAAGUCUCAGAAGAAAUACAGAAAGAAAUUCAGGACUUGGAGAAGACUCUAGAUGUUUUUAACAUAAUUUUAGCAAGGCAACAAGCACAAGUUGAGGUGAUUCGGUCUGGGCAAAAAUUAAGGAAAAAGUCUGCUGACACAGGCGAGAAACGUGGAGGCUGGUUUAGUGGGUUGUGGGGUAAGAAAGAGUCUAAGAAAAAGGACGAAGAAUCAUUGAUUCCUGAAACUAUUGAUGACCUUAUGACUCCAGAGGAAAAAGAUAAACUCUUCACUGCCAUUGGUUAUAGUGAGAGUACCCACAACCUAACUUUACCUAAGCAGUAUGUUGCCCAUAUUAUGACCCUGAAGUUAGUAAGCACCUCUGUUACGAUAAGAGAAAACAAGAAUAUUCCAGAAAUACUAAAAAUUCAGAUAAUUGGCCUGGGCACUCAAGUAUCUCAGCGACCAGGAGCACAAGCACUUAAGGUAGAAGCGAAAUUAGAACACUGGUAUAUAACAGGUUUGAGACAGCAGGAUAUUGUGCCAUCACUUGUGGCUUCAAUUGGUGACACUACAUCAUCCUUGCUUAAAAUUAAAUUUGAAACCAAUCCGGAGGAUAGUCCUGCUGACCAGACUCUGAUUGUUCAGUCCCAGCCUGUGGAGGUCAUCUAUGAUGCUAAAACUGUCAAUGCAGUGGUUGAAUUCUUUCAAUCAAAUAAGGGAUUGGAUCUUGAGCAAAUAACAUCAGCAACAUUGAUGAAGCUGGAAGAAAUUAAGGAGAGAACAGCUACAGGACUUACACAUAUUAUUGAAACUCGAAAAGUCCUUGAUUUAAGGAUAAAUCUGAAGCCUUCUUAUCUAGUAGUUCCACAGACGGGUUUCCACCAUGAAAAGUCAGAUCUUCUGAUUUUAGAUUUUGGUACAUUUCAGCUCAACAGUAAAGAUCAAGGUUUACAGAAGACUACUAAUUCAUCUCUGGAAGAAAUAAUGGAUAAGGCAUAUGACAAGUUUGAUGUUGAAAUAAAAAAUGUACAACUACUUUUUGCAAGAGCAGAGGAAACCUGGAAAAAGUGUCGAUUUCAGCAUCCAUCAACUAUGCAUAUAUUGCAACCCAUGGAUAUUCAUGUUGAGUUGGCUAAGGCCAUGGUAGAAAAAGACAUUAGAAUGGCCAGAUUUAAAGUGUCAGGAGGACUUCCUUUGAUGCAUGUGAGAAUUUCUGACCAGAAGAUGAAAGAUGUGCUAUAUUUGAUGAACAGUAUACCUUUGCCACAGAAAUCAUCAGCCCAGUCUCCAGAGAGACAGGUAUCCUCAAUUCCUAUUAUUUCAGGUGGUACAAAAGGUCUACUUGGUACUUCACUAUUGCUAGACACUGUGGAAUCAGAGUCUGAUGAUGAGUAUUUUGAUGCUGAAGAUGGAGAACCACAGACUUGUAAAAGUAUGAAAGGAUCAGAACUUAAAAAAGCUGCAGAGGUCCCAAAUGAGGAGCUCAUCAAUCUUCUACUCAAGUUUGAAAUUAAAGAAGUGAUUUUGGAAUUUACUAAACAGCAGAAAGAAGAAGAUACAAUUCUAGUAUUUAAUGUUACUCAGUUAGGAACAGAGGCCACAAUGAGAACAUUUGACUUAACUGUGGUAUCUUAUUUAAAGAAAAUCAGCUUGGAUUAUCAUGAAAUUGAAGGAUCCAAAAGGAAGCCCCUUCACUUGAUUAGCUCUUCUGACAAACCUGGAUUAGAUCUUUUGAAAGUGGAGUAUAUUAAGGCUGAUAAGAAUGGACCUAGUUUUCAAACUGCUUUUGGAAAAACUGAACAAACAGUUAAGGUGGCCUUUUCAUCUUUAAAUCUGUUGCUGCAAACACAAGCUCUUGUCGCUUCUAUUAAUUACCUCACAACCAUUAUUCCAUCUGAUGAUCAAAGCAUAAGUGUUGCUAAGGAGGUACAAAUUUCAACUGAAAAACAACAAAAAAAUUCAACUCUGCCAAAAGCGAUUGUAUCCUCCAGAGAUAGUGACAUUAUUGAUUUCAGGCUAUUUGCCAAGUUGAAUGCUUUCUGUGUCAUUGUUUGCAACGAAAAGAACAAUAUCGCCGAAAUCAAGAUUCAAGGACUGGAUUCCUCCCUUUCUCUCCAGUCAAGAAAGCAGUCACUUUUUGCCCGACUAGAAAAUAUUAUUGUCACAGAUGUUGAUCCAAAGACAGUUCAUAAGAAAGCUGUGUCAAUAAUGGGAAAUGAAGUUUUCCGUUUUAAUUUGGAUUUGUAUCCAGAUGCUACUGAGGGGGAUUUGUAUACUGACAUGUCCAAAGUGGAUGGUGUGCUGUCUCUGAAUGUUGGCUGUAUUCAGAUUGUCUAUCUUCAUAAAUUCCUUAUGUCACUUCUGAACUUCCUGAAUAAUUUCCAGACAGCCAAAGAGUCUCUGAGUGCUGCCACUGCCCAGGCUGCAGAAAGGGCUGCCACAAGUGUGAAAGAUCUUGCCCAGAGGAGUUUUCGUGUUUCCAUCAAUAUUGAUUUGAAAGCACCGGUUAUAGUCAUCCCACAGUCUUCUAUUUCCACCAAUGCAGUAGUGGUAGAUCUUGGGUUAAUCAGAGUUCAUAAUCAGUUCAGUCUGGUGUCUGAUGAAGACUACUUAAAUCCUCCAGUAAUUGAUAGAAUGGAUGUGCAGCUAACAAAGCUUACACUUUAUAGGACAGUGAUCCAGCCAGGCAUCUACCAUCCUGAUAUUCAGCUGUUGCACCCAAUUAACUUGGAAUUUCUUGUAAAUCGGAAUCUAGCUGCAUCUUGGUACCACAAGGUGCCUGUUGUGGAAAUUAAAGGACAUCUUGAUUCAAUGAAUGUUAGUCUAAAUCAAGAAGAUCUUAAUCUUUUAUUUAGGAUACUAACAGAAAAUCUCUGUGAGGGUACUGAAGACUUGGAUAAAGUGAAACCAAGAGUACAAGAGACAGGUGAAAUUAAAGAGCCCCUUGAAAUCUCUAUAUCACAAGAUGUACAUGAUUCAAAAAAUACUUUAACAACUGGAGUGGAAGAAAUUAGGUCUGUAGACAUCAUUAAUAUGCUGCUGAAUUUUGAAAUUAAAGAGGUUGUGGUUACUUUGAUGAAAAAAUCAGAAAAGAAAGGAAGGCCUUUACAUGAGCUAAAUGUCCUGCAACUUGGAAUGGAAGCUAAAGUUAAAACCUAUGACAUGACUGCUAAAGCUUAUCUAAAAAAAAUUAGUAUGCAGUGCUUUGAUUUCACUGACUCUAAAGGGGAACCUCUUCACAUUAUUAACUCUUCUAAUGUGACUGACGAACCCCUUCUGAAAAUGUUACUGACAAAGGCAGACAGUGAUGGACCAGAAUUUAAAACUAUUCAUGACAGUACCAAACAGAGACUGAAGGUUUCAUUUGCAUCCUUAGACUUAGUACUUCAUUUGGAAGCUUUACUUUCCUUCAUGGAUUUUUUAUCAUCUGCUGCUCCAUUCUCUGAGCCUUCCUCUUCUGAGAAGGAAUCCGAGCUGAAACCACUUGUGGGGGAGUCCAGAAGUAUCGCUGUCAAAGCUGUAUCCAGCAACAUUUCCCAAAAGGAUGUGUUUGAUUUAAAGAUCACAGCUGAAUUAAAUGCAUUUAAUGUCUUUGUCUGUGAUCAGAAGUGUAACAUUGCAGAUAUUAAAAUACAUGGAAUGGAUGCCUCUAUUUCUGUGAAGCCUAAGCAGACUGAUGUGUUUGCCAGACUUAAAGAUAUUAUAGUUAUGAAUGUAGAUUUGCAGUCCAUUCACAAAAAGGCUGUCUCUAUUUUGGGAGAUGAAGUCUUUAGGUUCCAACUGACUCUUUAUCCAGAUGCCACAGAAGGAGAGGCCUAUGCUGAUAUGUCCAAAGUAGACGGCAAACUUAGUUUUAAAGUGGGUUGUAUUCAGAUUGUUUAUGUUCAUAAAUUCUUCAUGUCUCUUUUGAACUUCCUCAACAAUUUCCAAACUGCUAAAGAAGCUUUGAGUACAGCCACAGUCCAGGCUGCAGAAAGAGCUGCUUCCAGCAUGAAAGACUUGGCUCAAAAGAGUUUCCGCCUUUUGAUGGAUAUUAAUUUGAAAGCACCAGUUAUUAUUAUUCCUCAGUCUUCAGUAUCACCUAAUGCUGUUAUAGCAGAUCUGGGUUUAAUCAGAGUUGAAAACAAGUUUAGCUUGGUUCCUAUGGAACAUUAUUCUCUUCCUCCAGUCAUUGAUAAAAUGAACAUCGAACUCACUCAGUUGAAGCUGUCAAGAACUAUUUUGCAGGCUAGCUUGCCACAAAAUGACAUUGAAAUUUUAAAACCAGUCAACAUGCUUUUGUCCAUACAGCGAAACUUAGCAGCAGCAUGGUAUGUGCAAAUUCCAGGGAUGGAGAUAAAAGGAAAACUAAAACCUAUGCAGGUUGCUCUCAGUGAAGAUGACUUGACAGUUUUAAUGAAAAUUUUGCUAGAAAAUCUUGGAGAAGCUUCCUCACAACCAAGCCCUACACAGUCUGUGCAGGAGACUGUAAGAGUGAGAAAAGUUGAUGUUUCAAGUGUACCUGACCAUCUCAAAGAACAAGAAGAUUGGACAGACUCAAAGCUCUCUAUGAACCAGAUUGUCAGUCUCCAAUUUGACUUUCACUUUGAAUCUCUUUCCAUUAUCCUUUAUAACAAUGAUAUCAACCAGGAAUCUGGAGUUGCAUUUCAUAAUGACAGUUUCCAACUUGGUGAACUCAGACUACAUCUUAUGGCCUCCUCAGGGAAGAUGUUUAAGGAUGGCUCAAUGAAUGUCAGCGUUAAACUUAAGACAUGCACCCUUGAUGAUCUCAGAGAAGGAAUUGAGAGAGCAACAUCGAGAAUGAUUGACAGAAAGAAUGACCAAGAUAACAACAGUUCUAUGAUUGAUAUAAGUUACAAACAAGACAAAAAUGGAAGUCAAAUUGAUGCUGUUCUUGACAAGCUGUAUGUAUGUGCCAGUGUGGAAUUUCUGAUGACUGUGGCAGAUUUCUUUAUCAAAGCUGUGCCUCAGAGUCCAGAAAAUGUGGCAAAAGAAACACAGAUUUUACCAAGACAGACUGCCACAGGGAAGGUCAAGAUAGAGAAAGAUGACUCUGUUAGACCAAAUAUGACUUUAAAGGCCAUGAUCACAGAUCCAGAAGUGGUAUUUGUUGCCAGCCUGACAAAGGCUGAUGCUCCUGCUCUGACAGCCUCGUUUCAGUGCAACCUUUCUCUGUCAACAUCCAAACUCGAACAGAUGAUGGAAGCUUCUGUGAGAGAUCUGAAAGUGCUCGCUUGCCCUUUUCUCAGAGAAAAGAGAGGGAAAAACAUUACCACAGUCUUGCAGCCCUGUUCUUUAUUUAUGGAAAAAUGUACGUGGGCUUCAGGAAAGCAAAAUAUAAAUAUUAUGGUUAAAGAAUUUAUAAUUAAGAUUUCACCCAUAAUUCUUAAUACUGUGUUGACAAUCAUGGCUGCAUUGUCUCCAAAAACAAAAGAAGAUGGAUCCAAAGAUACGUCUAAGGAAAUGGAAAAUCUUUGGGGUAUCAAAUCGAUUAAUGAUUAUAACACUUGGUUUCUUGGUGUUGACACGGCAACAGAAAUAACGGAAAGCUUCAAAGGCAUUGAACAUUCACUGAUAGAGGAAAAUUGUGGUGUUGUUGUAGAAUCCAUUCAAGUUACCUUAGAAUGUGGCCUUGGACAUCGAACUGUACCUUUAUUAUUGGCAGAGUCUAAGUUUUCAGGAAAUAUUAAAAAUUGGACUUCUCUAAUGGCUGCUGUUGCUGACGUGACACUACAGGUGCACUAUUACAAUGAGAUCCAUGCUGUCUGGGAGCCACUGAUUGAGAGAGUGGAGGGGAAGAGACAAUGGAAUUUAAGGCUUGAUGUAAAGAAGAACCCAGUUCAGGAUAAAAGUUUGCUGCCAGGAGAUGAUUUUAUUCCUGAGCCACAAAUGGCAAUUCAUAUUUCUUCAGGAAAUACAAUGAAUAUAACAAUAUCCAAAAGUUGUCUUAAUGUUUUCAACAAUUUAGCAAAAGGUUUUUCAGAGGGCACUGCUUCUACUUUUGACUACUCUUUAAAGGACAGAGCUCCUUUUACGGUAAAAAAUGCUGUAGGUGUUCCCAUUAAGGUGAAGCCCAAUUGUAAUCUCAGAGUAAUGGGCUUCCCUGAGAAAAGUGAUAUUUUUGAUGUUGAUGCUGGCCAGAAUUUGGAACUGGAGUAUGCCAGCAUGGUACCUUCAAGUCAAGGGAACCUAUCUAUAUUGAGCCGUCAAGAAAGCUCCUUCUUCACUCUGACCAUUGUACCUCAUGGAUAUACAGAAGUUGCAAAUAUCCCUGUGGCCAGACCUGGACGGCGAUUGUAUAAUGUACGGAAUCCCAAUGCCAGUCAUUCUGACUCUGUCUUGGUACAAAUUGAUGCAACUGAAGGGAAUAAAGUAAUUACCCUUCGCUCUCCUCUACAGAUCAAAAACCAUUUCUCCAUUGCAUUUAUCAUCUAUAAAUUUGUUAAGAAUGUUAAGCUAUUGGAGCGCAUUGGGAUAGCCAGACCUGAAGAGGAGUUCCAUGUUCCUUUAGAUUCAUAUAGAUGUCAAUUGUUUAUCCAGCCAGCUGGAAUCUUAGAGCAUCAGUACAAAGAAUCUACCACUUAUAUUUCCUGGAAGGAAGAACUUCAUAGGAGCAGGGAAGUCAGAUGCAUGUUGCAGUGUCCAUCAGUAGAAGUCAGCUUCUUACCUCUCAUAGUGAAUACAGUUGCUCUGCCUGAUGAAUUGAGCUACAUAUGUACACAUGGGGAAGACUGGGAUGUAGCUUACAUUAUUCAUCUUUAUCCUUCUCUCACUUUGCGGAAUCUUCUCCCAUAUUCCCUAAGAUAUUUACUUGAGGGAACAGCAGAAACUCAUGAGCUGGCAGAAGGCAGUACUGCUGAUGUUCUGCAUUCGAGAAUCAGUGGUGAAAUAAUGGAAUUAGUCCUGGUGAAAUACCAGGGCAAAAACUGGAAUGGACAUUUCCGCAUACGUGAUACACUACCAGAAUUCUUUCCUGUGUGUUUUUCUUCUGACUCCACAGAAGUGACGACAGUCGACCUGUCAGUCCACGUCAGGAGAAUUGGCAGCCGGAUGGUGCUGUCUGUCUUUAGUCCCUAUUGGUUAAUCAACAAGACUACCCGGGUUCUCCAGUAUCGUUCAGAAGAUAUUCAUGUGAAACAUCCAGCUGAUUUCAGGGAUAUUAUUUUAUUUUCUUUCAAGAAGAAGAACAUUUUUACUAAAAAUAAGGUACAAUUAAAAAUUUCAACCAGUGCCUGGUCCAGUAGUUUCUCAUUGGAUACAGUGGGAAGUUAUGGGUGUGUGAAGUGUCCUGCCAACAAUAUGGAGUACCUGGUUGGUGUUAGCAUCAAAAUGAGCAGUUUCAACCUUUCACGAAUAGUUACCCUGACUCCCUUUUGUACCAUUGCAAACAAGUCAUCAUUAGAACUAGAAGUUGGCGAGAUUGCAUCUGAUGGCUCAAUGCCAACUAAUAAAUGGAACUAUAUUGCUUCUUCAGAGUGCCUUCCAUUUUGGCCAGAAAGUUUGUCAGGCAAACUUUGUGUGAGAGUGGUGGGCUGUGAAGGAUCUUCCAAACCAUUCUUUUAUAACCGACAGGAUAAUGGCACUUUAUUGAGCUUAGAAGAUCUGAAUGGGGGUAUCUUGGUGGAUGUAAACACUGCCGAACAUUCAACUGUCAUAACUUUUUCUGAUUACCAUGAGGGAUCUGCACCUGCCUUGAUAAUGAACCAUACACCAUGGGACAUCCUCACAUACAAACAGAGUGGGUCACCAGAAGAAAUGGUCUUGCUGCCAAGACAGGCUCGACUUUUUGCCUGGGCAGAUCCUACUGGUACCAGAAAACUUACAUGGACAUAUGCAGCAAAUGUUGGGGAACAUGAUCUGUUAAAGGAUGGAUGUGGACAGUUUCCAUAUGAUGCAAACAUCCAGAUACACUGGGUAUCAUUUCUGGAUGGGCGCCAGAGAGUUUUGCUUUUCACCGAUGAUGUUGCCUUGGUUUCCAAAGCACUGCAGGCAGAAGAAAUGGAACAGGCUGAUUAUGAAAUAACCUUGUCUCUCCACAGUCUUGGGCUUUCACUGGUUAACAAUGAAAGCAAGCAGGAAGUUUCCUAUAUUGGGAUAACCAGUUCUGGUGUUGUUUGGGAGGUGAAACCAAAGCAGAAAUGGAAGCCAUUUAGUCAAAAGCAGAUAAUCUUAUUGGAACAAUCCUAUCAGAAACAUCAAAUAUCAAGAGACCAUGGCUGGAUUAAGCUAGAUAAUAAUUUUGAGGUCAAUUUUGAUAAAGAUCCAAUGGAAAUGCGCCUCCCUAUUCGUAGCCCUAUUAAACGAGACUUUUUAUCAGGAAUUCAGAUUGAAUUUAAGCAGUCUUCUCACCAGAGAAGUUUAAGGGCCAGGUUGUACUGGCUUCAGGUUGAUAAUCAGUUACCAGGUGCAAUGUUCCCUGUUGUAUUUCAUCCUGUUGCCCCUCCAAAAUCUAUUGCUUUAGAUUCAGAGCCCAAGCCUUUCAUUGAUGUGAGUGUCAUCACAAGAUUUAAUGAGUACAGUAAAGUCUUACAGUUCAAGUAUUUUAUGGUCCUCAUUCAGGAAAUGGCCUUAAAAAUUGAUCAAGGGUUUCUAGGAGCUAUUAUUGCACUGUUUACCCCAACAACAGACCCUGAAGCUGAAAGAAGACGGACAAAGUUAAUCCAACAAGAUAUUGAUGCUCUAAAUGCAGAAUUAAUGGAGACUUCAAUGACUGAUAUGUCAAUUCUUAGUUUCUUUGAACAUUUCCAUAUUUCUCCUGUGAAGUUGCAUUUGAGUUUGUCUUUGGGUUCCGGAGGUGAAGAAUCAGACAAAGAAAAACAGGAAAUGUUUGCAGUUCAUUCUGUCAACUUGCUGUUGAAAAGCAUAGGUGCUACUCUGACUGAUGUGGAUGACCUUAUAUUCAAACUUGCUUAUUAUGAAAUUCGAUAUCAGUUCUACAAGAGAGAUCAGCUUAUAUGGAGUGUUGUUAGGCAUUACAGUGAACAGUUCUUGAAACAGAUGUAUGUCCUUGUAUUGGGGUUAGAUGUACUUGGAAACCCAUUUGGAUUAAUUAGAGGUCUGUCUGAAGGAGUUGAAGCUUUAUUCUAUGAACCCUUCCAGGGUGCUGUUCAAGGCCCUGAAGAAUUUGCAGAGGGGUUAGUGAUUGGAGUGAGAAGCCUCUUUGGACACACAGUAGGUGGUGCAGCAGGAGUUGUAUCUCGAAUCACCGGUUCUGUUGGGAAAGGUUUGGCAGCAAUUACAAUGGACAAGGAAUAUCAGCAAAAAAGAAGAGAAGAGUUGAGUCGACAGCCCAGAGAUUUUGGAGACAGCCUGGCCAGAGGAGGAAAGGGCUUUCUGCGAGGAGUUGUUGGUGGAGUGACUGGAAUAAUAACAAAACCUGUGGAAGGUGCCAAAAAGGAAGGAGCUGCUGGAUUCUUUAAAGGAAUUGGAAAAGGGCUUGUGGGUGCUGUGGCCCGUCCAACUGGUGGAAUCGUAGAUAUGGCCAGUAGUACCUUCCAAGGCAUUCAGAGGGCAGCAGAAUCAACUGAGGAAGUAUCUAGCCUCCGUCCCCCUCGCCUGAUCCAUGAAGAUGGCAUCAUUCGUCCUUAUGACAGACAGGAAUCUGAGGGCUCUGACUUACUUGAGCAAGAACUGGAAAUACAGGAAUAAAUGUUUCCUAAACUACUACUUGAUUUCAUCCUUAAAAAUCAAAACAAACUGUGGUGUUAAUUGACUGUGUGUGAAUUCCAUUGUCAAUUUUAAUGAAAUUUUCUUUAAAACUCUCACCUCCAUCUGAACUUUUCAUAGUAGUGGGAUUGACUACAAAUAAAAACUUGUGGUAUUCCUGGUAAUACUGUCCAGAAAUAAGAGAUUAGUAUAAAAUAUUAAAGGAUGCAGAGAAUCAGCUCUCUUCUGCGUUUAAUAGAUGAAAGCCUUUAUUGAGCUCAGAAGCAGAUACUGUUACUAUCAUUUCGAAAAUUUUAUCUUAUGGUGUUCAUGUGCAUUUCAGGUAAAAUUGAAAAACAGGACAAUUAUUAUGUCCAAUUAAUAUGUUUAUGUUUGUGAGUCUUGAUGAUGGAAUUACAUAGCUUUCUGUUUCACAAAUGGCUCUAAAUUUGCUUAAGUUACGGGACUAUUACCUGGAGCAUCUGCUUUAAUAAUUGAAUUGUCAGUUGCUCUGAGCCUGCCCUUAGACCUCAAGUAAUAAAUAGUUGGCACAUGAAUUUUGAGGAUAUGUUUCCUCUUCCCUCUUUUUCCUAUUUAACCCCUUGGUACUGUUGCUAAAUAAAUGAUAGCCAUUUUAUAAUUAUGUUAUAUACAUUUUCAGCCUUUAGCAUUUCUGCUUUUCAAAAAUUGAAUCUCCUUGUUGGUUAUGCUUAUUUCAUAAUUAUUAGUUUUAAUUAAUGUAGAUAGAAGUUGAACAUGUAAUUAGGCAAAUUGCUGUGUGGCACUUGAAUACAUAGAUUUCUUUAUUUUCAAAAACCAACCUUUUGCUUUUAAAUCCUUAGAGAGGGUUUAUUAUCUUAGAGAAAAAAUAAUUAUAAUCAUUAUUUUUGAAAUUAGUAUCCUCUUAAUUCUCAACAUAAGUUAUGUUUCAAUUUCUUUUUUUUGUAAUAAAUGAUGGAAAUGUUUAACAAUGUCUUAUCUAGCAACUUUCAUGCUUCUCCUCAGAAAUGAAGCCAAAGUAUAAACUUAGAUUUAAUGUGUUGUAUAUUUGAAGAGAAUGAAACUAUUAACAUAUAAUUGUUCAGUUGGAUUAUGUAUUUUAAGGAUUGCAGUUAUCAAAAUAAUAAAUUGAAUGUUUUAUGUUUAACCACUUUAAAGAAGAAAGACUGACAUCCAAAAACCAGCGUGUGCUAGAUAUACAAAGGAAAUUACUUCUGUCCUUAAGGGACCAAGUAUAACAAAACAUGUAACUGUUAAAAGUAGCUGACAAACCUUUCUUGUGCCUAGAUAAUUUAGCAUUGGCAAAAAUGUCACCACAUGCAGUUUUCUAGGAGAGUCAAGCACAAAUAACUAAUUCAAGAUGCUGACUUAAAUCAUCUCCAAUAGUUACCCUUCCUGAGAUUCUAAAGUAACAAUUUUUAAUUUUACUGGUUAUAUUGCUGUUUUACUGAGACUUACUUUUAAGAACCCCUGUAACUUAAGAUUUUUUCUUAAUUGUUUUGUUUAGCUCUGUUAUUAAUUUUUUCCUUGUGAUAUCUUUUUAUAACUCUCUGUCAAAAAGCACAAAACUUCAAGAAACUUUUAAUUAUUUUGUCUGAACAUAUAAUCUUGUCUGAUUUCUUAGUUUUUAUUAAGAUAUCAGACAACUUUUAAAACUUUAGUGCAUUAUUAUAAUUACUGGAAGAAAAAGAAUGAUUAUACACUAAUGAGAGGACUUGGUAGUUUUUGUCGUGGAUGUCAAGUGUGGGCAUGGAUAAUUGAAAUAUUUAGGCUAUUUCAUUCUUUGCCCAUCUUGCUGUGAUCAGUUAGUUGGGUAAAAAUAUUUAUUGAUUAUUUAGACUGUACUGGAUAUACAAAAGAAGCCUUCUGUCCUUAAGGGACCGAGUAAAACAAAACAUGGAAAUAUUAAAGAGUAUUAGAGUAUAAAAGUAUAUCUUUUUAGCCCUUUGUAAUAUGGCCAAAUUCUAAAUAAUUUAUUUGGGGAUCUUUUGAUCCUCAUGUUCCUUUUUCUCCUAAGUACUACUUUGUAUUCUUUAAUAUGCAGCUUUGAGAGUUACUGAAUCAUAUAUUAUAUUUCCAUGAGAUGUACUAUUCUACUUAUCCUCUAAUCUUCAUAUAUAUAUACACACACACAUAUAUAUACACAUACAUAUAUACACACGUACAUAUAUGUACACAUACAGAUAUACAUACACACAAACACAUAUAUACACACAUACAUAUACACACAUAUAUAUACACAUACAAAUAUACACAUAUAUACACAUACAUAUAUAUACACACAUACAAAUAUACCCAUAUGUACACAUACAUAUAUACACAUACAUAUAUACACACACAUAUACACACAUAUAUACGCAAACAUACACAUAUUUACACAUACAUAUAUACAUACAUUAUAUGUAUGUAUAUAUAGUCAUUUAAUACUCAUUUUGGUUCACAUACUUAUGAUCAUGCAACGUUUAAAACAGCAUUUCUUGCUUUUUAGUUUUAGUUAUAUUUUUCCAUGUUCUUAGAAAUGCCUCAUUAACAUUUUUAAUUCUUGUAUUGCCAUCUAUUGAGGUGACAUUACAUUGUGUUUUUAUCUCGUCUUAAUUCAUGACAUUAAAUUAUUCUACUAACAGUAAUAAUGCUGUAAUAAACAUCAUUAUAGAUUUUGCUUUUUUAUAUCUUGUUUGCUUUUUCAUAUUUCCUUAGAAUUUACUUGAAAAAAUUGAAUUACUGGGUAAAGGGCUUUUGCAAAGUAUUGUUAAAUUCCUCGAGUUGCAUUUUUGGAAAGGGGACGUGAAUAUUUUAUCAACUAAUUUGGUCUCCCUGCUGCCAUUAGUGACUGAAUAUCUUAAUCUGAAUCUCAGAGUGUAGUGGGUUUUUAGUAGUGCUGAAGACAAGUUUUCUAAAGUGUAUUAUGGUGAUAAAUUAUAUUUUAAAAACUGUCAAUGGCUUGAAGCACAAUAGCCUAAUAACUAACGAAAAUACAUACAAGAUAGAAAGUGGGUAGUAUUUCUUGUACUUGCAUUUCAGAUCUAAAUAUUUUAACAUAUUUAAAUUUCAAGCUGCAGAUAAAUGCAUUACAUUAUUAAAUUCAUUUCCCAUUUUCUCUUUGAAGAAAUUAAGGCAAAAGUGUUAAAAGAUUUUAACUAAUUCGCACAAGUGAAUUGUGAAACAAGUAGCUAUUGCUGUGAAAUCUGCACUCCUCUCUGAGACUCAUUCUGAAGAUGAGAUCCCAGUUCUUUGUGGAUUCCUCUUCCUUAUUCAUGGCUUUUUGCAAUUGUCAAGGAAUGACUAGGUACCAAGCAACUUUAAAAAAUGUAUAUUUAAGCAUUGAAAUAAUAUCAAAUGUGAUUUCUCUGCUUGUGGUUAUAUUGAUUAUAUUAUCCUUUUAAUAAUAUUGGCAUUAUAUUCUUGGUCGUAAAAUGUCAAGGUCUUAUUUAUUCAGUAUAUUUAUGUUCUGUAUUUUCAUAUAUAUUAUCUAUUUUCAGCCAUGCAUUAUAUAUAAUGUCAGUAAUAGUAUUUCAUUAGCAUUCAUUAUAAAAAAACUCGUUUUUAAUAUUUGACUAAUUCAAGUCACAGUACUUUUGAGAUAGCUGAAAAGGAAAAUAAAUGUGUUUUAAUGUGCUACUA